ACAUUUUCAAGGAAUUCUUGAGAGGUUCUUGGAGAGAUUCUGGGAGCCAAACACUCCAUUGGGAUCCUAGCUGGAAUAUAAAGAAUGGCUUAUCAGUGGAGACCAUCGACAGUUGAGAAAAGAAGAAGCCCAAAAAGUACAAGAAUGAAAAUCGAGAGUUUUUAGAGAACAACUUGUAAUGGAGCCUUCAUCUCUUGAGCUGCCGGCUGACACAGUGCAGCGCAUUGCGGCUGAACUCAAAUGCCACCCAACGGAUGAGAGGGUGGCUCUCCACCUAGAUGAGGAAGAUAAGCUGAGGCACUUCAGGGAGUGCUUUUAUAUUCCCAAAAUACAGGAUCUGCCUCCAGUUGAUUUAUCAUUAGUGAAUAAAGAUGAAAAUGCCAUCUAUUUCUUGGGAAAUUCUCUUGGCCUUCAACCAAAAAUGGUUAAAACAUAUCUUGAAGAAGAACUAGAUAAGUGGGCCAAAAUAGCAGCCUAUGGUCAUGAAGUGGGGAAGCGUCCUUGGAUUACAGGAGAUGAGAGUAUUGUAGGCCUUAUGAAGGACAUUGUAGGAGCCAAUGAGAAAGAAAUAGCCCUAAUGAAUGCUUUGACUGUAAAUUUACAUCUUCUAAUGUUAUCAUUUUUUAAGCCUACGCCAAAACGAUAUAAAAUUCUUCUAGAAGCCAAAGCCUUCCCUUCUGAUCAUUAUGCUAUUGAGUCACAACUACAACUUCACGGACUUAACAUUGAAGAAAGUAUGCGGAUGAUAAAGCCAAGAGAGGGGGAAGAAACCUUAAGAAUAGAGGAUAUCCUUGAAGUAAUUGAGAAGGAAGGAGACUCAAUUGCAGUGAUCCUGUUCAGUGGGGUGCAUUUUUACACUGGACAGCACUUUAAUAUUCCUGCCAUCACAAAAGCUGGACAAGCGAAGGGUUGUUAUGUUGGCUUUGAUCUAGCACAUGCAGUUGGAAAUGUUGAACUCUACUUACAUGACUGGGGAGUUGAUUUUGCCUGCUGGUGUUCCUACAAGUAUUUAAAUGCAGGAGCAGGAGGAAUUGCUGGUGCCUUCAUUCAUGAAAAGCAUGCCCAUACGAUUAAACCUGCAUUAGUGGGAUGGUUUGGCCAUGAACUCAGCACCAGAUUUAAGAUGGAUAACAAACUGCAGUUAAUCCCUGGGGUCUGUGGAUUCCGAAUUUCAAAUCCUCCCAUUUUGUUGGUCUGUUCCUUGCAUGCUAGUUUAGAGAUCUUUAAGCAAGCGACAAUGAAGGCAUUGCGGAAAAAAUCUGUUUUGCUAACUGGCUAUCUGGAAUACCUGAUCAAGCAUAACUAUGGCAAAGAUAAAGCAGCAACCAAGAAACCAGUUGUGAACAUAAUUACUCCGUCUCAUGUAGAGGAGCGGGGGUGCCAGCUAACAAUAACAUUUUCUGUUCCAAACAAAGAUGUUUUCCAAGAACUAGAAAAAAGAGGAGUGGUUUGUGACAAGCGGAAUCCAAAUGGCAUUCGAGUGGCUCCAGUUCCUCUCUAUAAUUCUUUCCAUGAUGUUUAUAAAUUUACCAAUCUGCUCACUUCUAUACUUGACUCUGCAGAAACAAAAAAUUAGCAGUGUUUUCUAGAACAACUUAAGCAAAUUAUACUGAAAGCUGCUGUGGUUAUUUCAGUAUUAUUCGAUUUUUAAUUAUUGAAAGUAUGUCACCAUUGACCACAUGUAACUAACAAUAAAUAAUAUACCUUACAGAAAAUCUGAUAUAAUUUUUCAGAGUCUGUGGCACUAAGGAGUCCACAGGGCUGCCUAGGUGCUUUGUGUUUGGGGGACCAAAACUGUGUUGGUUCAAGUAUUAUCUAUACAGUCUCUAUAAGCUGUCACAUUUCAUGGUCAUUGAAAUGUUUUAUGUUGGUUUAAUUUCUGAUUUAACUGACAACUUCAUAAUGUAUGUGCAAUUAUUGUGUCAAAUUUAGAAAUAUUACUUUAGCUUCAAUUUACCAAGGAGUUUCUUUGAAGCAUUGUAGUCUGAUAUAUAUAUAUAUAUAUAUAUAUAUAUAUAUAUAUAUAUAUAUAUAUGUGUGUGUGUGUGUGUGUAUAUAUAUAUAUAUAUAUCAUAUAUAUAUGAUAGUGGCUUUCAAAUUUUUUUGGGUACAAUCCACAUUGCUCCUGCUGAUCUGUAAUAUCAGAAACCAGUAUUUAUGUGAAUAUAUGAGAAAUAUUAUUGAUUCUAAGAUAUUUUAUCAUAUUUUAACAUCUUUGAAAGAGGACCCAUCUUUCAAUUUUCGAUCAAUAGUUUCUUACAGUCACCAUUGGCCAUCUUUCUCGUUACCAUCUAUGAAAUUAGCAUGCAUCUCAAAUAAACAGUUACCAUCUUCUAUUUGAUAAAAUAGUCUAAAUAGCAAAAAUAAAAGUUUUUACAAUUAUUUGCCUGUGCUCUAAUAGGUACUAUUCUAUUUUAUCUCAUAAGAAAUGUUGGAAACUCAUUAUAUUGAUUUCCUUACCCACUCAUGGGCCCUAAUUCACACUUUUUAAGAAUGUUUCUUUCUUUAAUGUUAUCAUAAUCUCUUACUUUUUAAAUGAGAACUUCCCCUAAUAUAAGAGCUUAGAUAUUAUAUUACUAUGUUUCCAUAGUAAAUAAAUAACCCCAAGAUCUUUUUGGGGAUUAGAGAUAUAAGAAAUAUGUGCUCCAUCUCUUGACAUCUUUAUCUCAAAUCUAUGGACCUUUCUUACCCACUGUGAAAAACCUAAAGUUACACUUAGCCCUGUUGGACUUACCUAGUUUUCAAUUGUUGAUGCCACAAUCAUUAUUUAUAAGUUGACAAAAUAGUGUAGAUUUGUAUACAUAGUCAACAAAAAGAGUGACAUAAUUAUUGCCUCCAAUUAAACAAGUUUGAAUGAAAUAAACAAACUUAGAUAAACACUUCGGAUGGUAGACGUAAACAAUAAUAUGUGGAACUCCAACAUCAACACCUACCAAUACCAGUAACUACUGAUAUUUAUCAUGUACUUACCAUGUACCAUGUAUUGUGCUACAUUACUCAUGUUAUCUCCCUUAAUUGAGUGGCUACAUACUGCUUUAGCAAAUCUUCCUACUGUAACUAAUCCUCAUAGAUGGAAGAGUUCUCAAAACCUUAAAACUCAUGCAUAAGUGGAUUCAUAUACAUAUAUAAAAAUAUAUAUAAAUAUAUAUACUUUAUAUAUAUUUAUAUUUAUAUAUUUAUAUAUUUAUAUUUUAAUAUAUUUAUAUAAAUAUAUAUAAAGUAUAAUAUAUAUAAAGUAUAAAUAUAUAUAUAUUUAUACUUUAAGUUCUUGGAUACACGUGCAGAACAUGCAGGUUUGUUACAUAGGUAUACAUGUGCCGUGGUGGAUUGCUGCACCCAUCAACCCGUCAUCUACAUCAGGUAUUUCUCCUAAUGCUCACCCUCCUCUUAUCCCCAACUACCCAAAAGGACCUGGUGUGUGAUGUUCCCCUCCCUGUGUUCAUAUGUUCUCAUUGUUCAACUCUCACUUAUGGGUAAGAACAUGCAGUGUUUGAUUUUCUGUUCCUCUGUUAGUUUGCUGAGAAUGAUGGUUUCCAGCUUCAUCCAUGUCCCUGCAAAGGACAUGAACUCAUUCUUUUUUAUGGCUGCAUAGUAUUCCAUGGUAUAUAUGUGCCACAUUUUCUUUAUCCAGUCUAUCAUUGAUGGCCAUUUGAGUUGGUUCCAAGUCUUCGCUAUUGUGAAUAGUGCUGCAAUGAACAUAUGUGUGCAUGUGUCUUUAUAGUAGAAUGAUUUAUAAUCCUUAGGGUAUACCCAGUAAUGGGAUUGCUGGGUUAAAUGGUAUUUCUGGUUCUAGAUCCUCGAGGAAUUGCCACACUGUCUUCCACAAUGGUUGAACUAAUUUAUACUCCCACCAACAGUGUAAAAGCAUUCCUAUUUCUCCACAUCCUCUCAGCAUCUGUUGUUUCUUGACUUUUUAAUGAUUAGCAUUCUAACUGGCGUGAGAUGGUAUUUCAUUGUGGUUUUGAUUUGCAUUUCUCUAAUGACCAGUGAUGAUGAGUUUUUUUUCAUAUAUUUGUUGGCCGCAUAAAUGUCUUCUUUUGAGAAGUGUCUGUUCGUAUCCUUCACCCACUUUUUGAUGGGGUUGUGUUUUUCUUGUAAAUUUAUUUAAGUCCCUUGUAGAUUCUGGAUAUUUUCCCUUUGUCAGAUGGAUAGAUUGCAAAAAUUUUCUCCCGUUCUGUAGGUUGCCCGAUCACUCUGAUGAUAGUUUCUUUUGCUGUGUAGAAGCUCUUUAGUUUAAUCAGGUUCCAUUUGUCAGUUUUGGCUUUUGUUGCAAUUGCUUUUGGUGUUUUAGUCUUAAAUUCUUUGCCCAUGCCUAUGUCCUGAAUGGUAUUGCCUAGAUAUUCUUCUAGGGUUUUUUUUUUGGCUUUAGGUCUUGCAGUUAAGUCUUUAAUCUAUCUUGAGUUAAUUUUUGUAUAAGAUAUAAGAAAGGGGUCCAGUUUCAGUUUUCUGCAUAUGGCUAGCCAGUUUUCCCAACACUAUUUAUUAAAUAGGGAAUCUUUUCCCCAUUGCUUGUUUUUGUCAGGUUUAUCAAAGAUCAGAUGGUUGUAAAUGUGUGGUGUUAUUUCUGAGGCCUCUGUUUUGUUCCAUUGGUCUAUAUGUCUGUUUUUGUUCAGUACCAUGCUGUUUUGUUUACUAUAGCCUUGUAGUAUAGUUUGAAGUCAGGUAGUGUGAUGCCUCCAGCUUUGUUCUUUUUGCUUAGGAUUGUCUUGGCAAUACAGGUUCUUUUUUGGUUCCAUAUGAAAUUUAAAGUAGUUUUUUCUAAUUCUGUGAAGAAAGACAAUGGUAGCUUGAUGGAAAUAGCAUUGAAUCUAUAAAUUACUCUCAGCAAUAUGGCCAUUUUCAGGAUAUUGAUUCUUCCUAUCUAUGAGCAUGGAAUGUUUUUCCAUUUGUUUGUGUCCUCUCUGGUAUCCUUGAGCAGUGGUUUGUAGUUCUCAUUGAAGUAGUCCUUCACAUCCCUUGUAAGUUGUAUUCCUAGGUAUUUUAUUCUCUUUGCAGCAAUUGUGAAUGGGAGUUCACUCAUGAUUUGGUUCUCUGUUUGUCCUAUAUACAUAUGUUGGUAUAUAGGAAUGCUUUUAUUUUAAAGAUGGAAGAUGAUGUCUCUCUAUGUAACUCAGGCAGGUCUCAAACUCCUGGGCUCAAAUGAUCCUCCUACCUUAACCUCCUGAGUAGCUGAGACUUUAGUCACACACCACCAUGCCUGACCAGGAAUUGUUUUUCAACUUCAUAGUGGUAAACAAAACAUAUGUGUUUUCAGUUCUCAUGGAACAAGCAGCUUAGUAGGAGAAACAUAUGUUGAACUUGUAAGCAGAGAAGUAAAUCUAUAAUGACAAAUCAUAAUUUCUGAAGGGUAUUAAUUAGAUGUUUGAGUGAGGGGAAAUAUUGGAAGGUGCUCAUAAGUUUAUAAAUGUUCUAAAAUAUUUCAUGCUAAUCACAUUAAAAUUAUAUCAAAGUAUAUAAACAUAUCAUGGAAAACAUAAUCAGCACCAUGUACUCAACACCUAGGUUAAAAAAUAGCAUUAAAAAUUCUCUUUCCAGCUCACAUUCUGCUCCCUCCCCAAAUCCACAGAUAACCAUCGAAUUAUAUUUUGUUUUCUUCAUUCCCUUACUUUCUUUAAGUUUUACACCCAUGUAUGUACCCAUAAAAAUCUAUUAGCUAAUUUUGGUUGUGCAUGAAUAUUGUAUCAAUGCAAUUAUACUGUAUAUAUUCUGCUUUUGCACAUAUUUUUAGAUUCAUCCAUUUGUGGCAUGUAGCUUUCCAUUCAUUUUCACUGCUGCUCAGUAUUGUAUUACAAAUUUUACAUUUGUUUUAGGGAAGAGUCAUAAACCAUCUUUAAGUUCUCCUAUGUUACAAGUAAUUUUGUAAAUGAUGUGAGGUGGUGAUUCUAUUUCAUUUUUUCCCAUAUAGAUAAUUUAUAUUAUUAAUAAUUCCUUCUAUUUCAUAAGCCAGGUUUCUAUAUAUCUAUAUAAAUAUAGAUAUGUAGAUAUAUGAAAGCAAUAUAUAUAUGGAUGUCUUUCUGGGCUAUCUGUACUUUCACACUGGCUAAUUUGCUUGUUUUUUCAUCAAUACUUCACUUCCUUAAUUACUACAACAUAGCAGGGCCUGGCAUCUGCUAGAUUAAAUCUCUCAGCUUCUUUUUAUUAAGAUUGCCCUGAAUUGUCCUGGUUAUCCUGGGCCCCCUACUUUUUUUAUAUUUUUGAAUACAUCUAAAUAAAUUUAGAAUAAAUCUAUUGUGUUCCAUAAAACCCCUGUUGGGAUUUCAAUUGAACUGCAAUUAAAUUUUAGAUCAGUUUUGGAAGAAUUGACUCAAUAGUGAGCCUUCCUACCCAAGACCAUGGCAUUUAUUUUCAUUUAUUUAUGAUUUCUUUAAUGCUUCUCAAAAUUUUUUAUUUUCUCUAUUAUGGAAACGCACAUUUAUAGUUUGACAAAUUCCUAAGUACUUCUAAUUUUAUUGUCAUUCCACAUUAUCUUUUUUGUUGUUGUUUUAAAAGACAGGGUCUCCCUCUGUCACCCAGGCUGGAGUGUACUGAUGUGAUUAUAGCUCACUGCAGUCUCAACCUCCUGGGCUCAAGUGAUCCUCCCACGUCAGCCUGUGGAGUAGCUAGGACUACAGGCAUGUGCCACAAUGCCUGGCUCAUUUUUAAGUGUUAAGUUAAAAAAAGUUGUAGAAACAGUGUUUUGCUACAUUUCCCAGGCUGGUCUCAAACUCCUGGCCCCAAGCAAUCUUCCUGCCUCAGCUUCCCAUAUUCGGAUUAUACGCAUGAGGCAUUGCACCAGCCCCAUGUGUUAUCUUUUAUAAAAUUUAACAUUUAACUGAUAAUUGAUACUGUAUAUACAUGAAUUCAAUUGGUAUCUAUUUUUAAUAUGGGAAAUUUUAUGCAAAUGAGCACAUUUUUCUCCCUUCCUUCCUUCCUUCUUUCCUUGUUCUCUUUCUUUCUCUCUCUUUCUCUUUCUCUCUUUCUUUCUUUCUUUCUUUCUCACAGGGUGUCACUCUGUUGCCCAGGCGGAGUGCAGUGGCACAUGAUCAUAGCUCACUGCAACCUCCAACUCAAACACUUGAGUGAUCCUCUGUCCCCCGUUUCCCAAGCAGCUGGGACUACAGGCACAUGCCACGAUGCCAAGCUAAUUUUUAAAAAUAAUUUUUUUUGUAGAUUCAGAGUCUUGCUAUGUUGCCCAGGCUAAUCUCAAACUCCUGGCCUCAAGCAGUCCUCCCUCCUCAGCCUCCCAUUACAGGCAUAAGCUGCCACUCCUGGACCUCUUUUUUUUUUUUUUUUUUUUUUUUUUGAGGCAGUCUCUCUCUGUCACCCAGGCUGGAGUAUAGUGGCACGAUCUCAGCUCACUGCGGGUUCAAGCAAUUUUCAUGCCUCAGCCUCCCAAGUAGCUGGGAUUACAGGCAUGGGCCACUAUGCCCAGCUAAUUUUUGUAUUUUUCAUAGAGACAGGAUUUCACCAUGUUGGCUAGGCUGGUAUCAAACUCCUGACUUCAGGUGAUCCGCCCACUUUGACCUUCCAAAAUGCUGGGAUUACGUGUGAGCCACCAAACCCAGCCCCUCAUUUUCUUUUUGAUUUUUAUUUAUUUUCCUCUGUUUUUCUUCUUUUGGAUUUAGGGAUGUGUGUGUGGAGGUGUAUUGAGUCCGUUUUUUCUUUCUAUUUGUGUGGAAAUUAUACACUUAUUCUUUGUUAUUUUAGCAAUUACUCUGGCUAUUUUAACAUGCAAAUAUAAUGAAGUUUAGAAUUAGCCAUUUUUUAUAACUCUCCUUCUGACUAGUUGAAGAAAUGAGAAUGCUUUAACAUCAAACAGCCAACUCUUUACUUAUACACUAUUGCUAUUCAUUAUAGCAUUUUUAGUCUAGCUUCCUCCCUCCUCUUUCUCUCUCUCUCUCUCUGUCUCUCUCUCUCUCACUAAUGUUUGCUAUUUCUCCCUACAAUUCAGAAUUUUAUUUAUGGAUGAAGUACAUAUAUAAUUUAUUACAAUUCAUUUUAAUGAAAAACUUUUAGUGGUAAAUUGUAUUAGUCUUUGGGAAAAAACAUUUAUUGAUACCAUUUUCUCAUUACUUAAAAAUAGUUUCACUUCAUAUAGAAUUCUAUGUCGACAGUAAUUUUCUUUCAGGAAGUAGAAAAUAUUAAGUUACAGUAUUUUGGCUUCCAUUACUGCUGUUAAGCAUUCAGAUCAUCAGAGAAAUGCAAAUCAGAACCACAAUGAGAUGCCAUCUCAUGCCAGUCAGAAUGGCAAUCAUUAAAAAGUCAGGAAACAAUAGAUGCUGGUGAGGCUGUGGAGAAAUAAGAAUGCUUUUACACUGUUAGUGGGAAUGUAAAUUAGUUCAACCAUUGCUCUUAAGGGCUCUUUGUCUUUAAUGAUCCGCAUUUUUAUUAUGAUGUGUCUAGGCAGUUAUUAUUGUGUUUAUUCUAUUUCUUUAUUUGCUGUCUAUCCAAGAUUUGAGGAUUAAUUUUUUAAUUUCUAGAAAAUUCAGAAGUAUUAUUUAUUUAUUCAAUUAUUACCUCUUUCUAUUAUUUCCUUUUUAAAAUAAAAGGGUAUAUGUUAGAAUUUUUCACUCUCUCCUUUAUGCCUUUAACUUCAUAUUUUCUAUUUCUUUGAAUUUCUGGGCUGCAUUCUUAAGAAUUCUAAAACAUAUAUUUUAGUUUCUAAAAGUUUCAUUAGAUUUCUGUUCAAAAUUCCUUCCAUUUGUGAUCUUUCGAAUGUGCUUCUGCUUUAGGCAUUAGUAGUGGACAUUCUGGUUCCCCAUUGAGCUUCCCUGCAUCAGCUGUUUUGCCUGGUGGCUGCCACCAACGCUUUUAGCUACCUCCCUCCUCAAACUUUGGGGUCAGGCCACACACUAUAAAGGAUUGGAAAAAAAAAUGAAAAUAUGAAAAACUUACACUUUGUAUCAGUCAGGAGAAGGAUAAUCUUCACACUACAGUUUAUGCUUCAGAAGCCACCCCUUCUCUGUGGAUUAGACCAUGACUAGAAGUUUCCUGAGACCAUCCCUUGCCCAGCUCUUUUGGUGAUCCCCUUCACUUCCUCUGUUACAGGUUUCCCUGAUGAGCACUCCUUCAAUAAAACAUAGUCAUCCAAAUCCCAAUCUCAAGCACGGUGUCACGGGAACCUGAUCUAAGUCAGCAUUUUCUUUAUUCUUAAUCACAACUAGUUGAUAGUCCAUAUCUAAUAUAUAAUGAAUGUACAGUUGUUUCUGUUGGAGUUCACAUAUGAUGCCUUGUUUCCUUUGUAGUUUUGUGAUUGAUAGCUUCGAACUGCUCAUUUACCUUGACCUUUUGAAUUCUUUGAAAACUGAGUUAAGUCUGAUUUUCCAGAGUUUUUAUGUUUGCUUCUGUCAGUUGCAGAGAAUCAAUGAGAAGAACACUUUAAAUUCUUGUUUUCGGUUUUUUUCCAAUCACAUAAGUAGGAUUUACCUGAAUAUAUAUAUAAUAUAUAAACAUAUAUUUAUAUAAAAUAAAAACAUAUAAAAUAUGAAAUAUAUAAUACAGUAUAAAAUCUAUUUUAUGUAAAAUCUAUUUUAUGUAAACAUGAUAAUUAAAUAUAUAUUUAAAUAAUAUAAAUAUAAUAAAUAUUUGAAGCAAUUGUAUUUUUUAAAAAUUUCUUCUAAAGAAAACCAGGAUACAUGUGCAGAACCUGCAGGUUUGUUACAUAGGUAUACGUGUGCCAUGGUGGUUUGCUGCACCUAUUGACCCGUCCUCUAAGUUCCCUCCCCUCACCUCCCACCCCCCAGCAGGCCCUGGUGUGUGUUGUUCCCCUCUCUGUGUCCAUGUAUUCUCGCCUCCCACUUAUGAGUGAGAACACGCGAUGUUUGGUUUUCUGUUCCUGUGUUAAUUUGCUGAGGAUGAUAGCUUCCAGCUUCAUCCACGUCCCUGCAAAGGACAUGAUCUCAUUCCUCAAUACUAUGGCUACGUAGUAUUCCAUGGUGUAUAUAUACCACAUUUUCUUCAUCCAGUCAUGCAAAUUUAUAUGAAUGUCAAUUCUUUUAUAGUGAUCUUCUGGGGCUAUUACAAUAUAUAGGGCUGUUUUUUUAAAACUAAUUAUAUUUAUUUCAUGUUGCUUUAACUUAUUAAAAAACAGACUGAAGAAAGACUGGGUGUGAAGUCAGUAAAUUAAUUUCAAAUUAAAUAAACUUUUCUACAGCUAUUUUAUGCUCAAUAACUUUCUACUUAUUCUUGAGUUCAAAACUAUAUGGGUUCACAUUUAAAUUAUAUAGUGUAUUUUCUCCAUAAACUGAAGUUGUUAGAACAUUGAUUUUUUUAAGUAAAUGGAUUUUUGCACCACUUCAAGAAAGAAACCUUCAAACAGCCUGGAAAUAUCACAUCAAUAAAGCACAACCUGGGAAUCAAAGUAUUAGGGUACCUUGUUACUGAGAUUAUGGAUGUGAUGCUUCUGUGGGCCAUUAGCAUGUGCACUGUGUGUAUGAUAUGCUCUAUGUUCUCUUCCCACUAAUAAUUUUAUUUUUAAUUUCAGCAAGAUUUAGUCUCAAAUAACACAAUAAUAAUGGAGGUCAUUGUGAAGUAGUGGAUGUAAAUAGAUCUGAUGUGGUUUUGGUUUAUUGCAGUAAUUGUUUUGACUAAUUCUCUAGUUUUUCAACUUUUGAUUGUUUAAGAUGGUUCUUGAGUCCUUUUGACAUGACCCUAUCUAUUUUUGAUAACUUCAUAGCCUUUAGUAUAAAAACAGGUAGGCUUAUAUUACAUAUUUCCAACUUCAAACUUGUUAUUUAUUUAUCUAAGACUAUACAGUUCUUUUCAGAGAAAAACCUUCUUUAUAAACCAGAAUCUUAACAGGAAGAGUGCUCAUUUUAAUUGAGCUGAUCAUGUUUCUAGGAUUUUUUAGUUAAAAGAAAAUACAUAUUUUAAAAAUAUAAAUUAUAUUUUUAUUUCAUAGUGGUAUUUUCAAUUUUGUCUGGGAUAAUAAGAUGUUUUAUUUAACUUGUUUGAUUUUGUAGUUUUAUCUUUGUGGGAAGGACCUGGUAAGAGGUAAUUGAAUCAUGGGGGCAGGACUUUCCCAUGAUGUUCUCAUGAUAAUGAAUAAGUUUCAUGAGAUCUGUUGGUUUCAUAAUGUGGAGUUUCCCUGCAAAGGCUCUUGUCCUGUCUGUGCCAUUUGAGACAUGCCUUUCAACUUCUGCCCUGAUUGUGAGGCCUCCCCCGCCAUGUGGAAUUGGGUCUUACUUUUGUAAAUUGCCCAGUCUCAGGUAUGUCUUUAUCAGCAGCCUGAAAACUGACUAAUAUAGUAAGUUGGCACCAGUAGAGAGGGGCACUGCUGAAAAGGUACCCGAAUAUGUGGAAGCAACUUUAAACUGGGUAACAGGCAGAGGUUGGAAUGGUUUGGAGGGCUCAUAAGAAGACAGGAAAGUGUGGGAAAUUUGGAACUCCCUAGAGACUUGUUGAAUGGCUUUAACCAAAAUGCUGAUAAUAAUAUGAACAAUGAAGUCCAGGCUGAGGUGGUCUCAGACAAAGAUAAGGAACUUCUUGGGAACUGGAGCAAAGGUGACUCUUGUUAUGUUUUAGACAUAAAGCAAAGAGACUGGAGGCAUUUUGCCCCUGCCCUAGAGAUUUGUGGGACAUUAAACUUGAGACAGAUUAUUUAGGGUAUCUGGAGGAAGAAAUUUUUAUGCAGCAAAGCAUUCAAGAGGUGACUUGGUUGCUAUUAAAGGCAUUCAGUUUUAAAAGGGAAAUACAGCAUAAAAGUUCAGAAAAUUUUCAGCCUGACAAUGCAGUAGAAAAGGAAAACCAAUUUUCUGAGGAGAAAUUUAAGCUGGCUGCAGACAUUUACAUAAGUAACAAGAAGCUGAAUGUUAAUCACUAAGACAAUGAGGAAAAUGUCUCCAGGGCAUGUCAGAGACCUUUGUGGCAGCCCCUCCCAUCACAGACCAGGAGCUUUAGAAGGAAAAAUGGCUUCGUGGGCUGGUCACAGGGUCCCUCUGCUGUGUGCAGUCUAGGGACUUGGUGCCCUGUGUCCCAGCAGCUCCAUCCAUGACUAAAAGGGGCCAAGGUACAGCUUGGGCUGUGGCUUCAGAGGGUGGAAGCCCCAAGUCUUGGCAGCUUCCAUAUGGUGUUGAGCCUGGGUUCACAGAAGUCAAGAACUGAGGUUUGGGAACUUACACCAAGAUUUCAGAGGAUGUAUGGAAAUGCCUGGAUGCCCAGGCAGAAGUUUGCUGCAGGGGCAAGGCCCUCAUGGAGAACCUCUGCUAGGGCAGUGAAGAAGGGAAAAGUAUGGUGGGAGCCCCCAUACAGAGUCCCUACUGAGGCACCACCUAGUGGAGCUUUGAGAAGAGGGCCACUGUCCUCCAGAACUCAGGAUGGUAAAUCCACCACGCACCUGGAAAAGCUGCAGACAAUUCCAGCCUGUUAAAGCAGCCAGGAGGGGGCUAUACCCUGCAAAGCCACAGGGGCGGACCUGCUCAAGGCUGUGGGAGACCACCUCUUGCAUCAGUGUGACCUGGAUGUGAGACAUGGAGUCAAAGGAGAUCAUUUUGGAGCUUUAAGAUUUGACUGCCCCACUGGAUUUCAGACUUUCAUGGGGCCUGUAGCCCCUUCGUUUUGGCCAAUGCCUCCCAUUUGGAGUGGCUGUAUUUACCCAAUGCCUGUAUCCCCAUUGUAUCUAGGAAGUAACUAACUUGCUUUUGAUUUUACAGGCCCAUAGGUGGAAGGGCGAUGUUUCUUUCUGGAGGCUCCAGGGAGAACUCUGUUUUCUUACCUUUUCUGGAUUCUAGAGGCUUCCCACAAUCCUUGGCUUAAGGUCCAUCUUUAAGCUUUGUCUCUGAUGAGACUUUGGACUGCGGACUUUUGAGUUAAUGCUGAAAUGAGUUAAGACUUUGGGUGACUGUUGCGAAGACAUGAUUGGUUUUGAAAUGUGAGAACAUUUAAGAGGGGCCAGGGGCAGAAUGAUAUGGUUUGACUUUGUCCGCAGUCAAAUCUCAUCUUGAAUUUCUAUGUGUUUGGAGAGGUACCCGGUGGGAGGUAAUUGAAUCAUGAGGGCAGGUCUUUUCUGUGCUGUUCUCAUGAUGGUGAGUAAGUCUCAUGAGAUCUGAUGGUUUUAUAAAGGGGAGUUUCCCUGCCCAAGUUCUUCUCUUGUCUGCCAUCAUGUGCGAUGUGCCUUUCACCUCUGCCAUGAUUAUGAGGCCUCCCUGGCCAUGUGGAACUGUGAGUCCAUUAAACCUCUUUCUUUUGUAAAUUGCCCAAUCUUGGGAAUGUCUUUAUCAGCAGUGGGAAAACGGAUUAAUAUACUAAUUUAUAGCUAGUAGGUAAAAAGCCAGGGACUUGCCAUUAGCGUUGGAAGUGGGGUUGUGGGGGCAGUCUUGUGGAACUGAGCCCUUAACCUGUGGGGUUGAAUGAUAUCUCCAGGUAUAUCAUGUCAGAAUUGAAUUCAAUUAGAGGAUACCUAGCUUGCGUUCAAUGCAGAAUUGCUUGCUGGUGAGGAGAAAUCCCUAUACACAUUUUGGUGACCAGAGGUAAAGCAUUUUAUGUUGAUUCUUGAGUGAGAGAGUAGAAAUAACACUGGUUUUUUCCCUAUGUCCUUACAACCACCAAUUGGAUACAUUGUUUCAGUAUUUUGAAAUUUUUCAUUUAAUUUUUAUAAAUUUUCUUUUUAAAUUUUAGAUUCUACAAUAUCUCCAAUUCUUCAGUUUAUUCCCUCUUACUAUGUAUAAGUAUUUCCCCAAGUUUCACUUUAUCUUUCUAUUACUUUUUUUACAUAAUAGAGCUAUAAAGGCAAUUCACAAUUCUCUCUUUUCUCAUAUAUAAUAUAGAGCAUAUUAUAAAUACUCUACUUUGGAAAAUUAUUCUUUAUAGGAAAUUACAGAUAAUAUUUGAUGAAGAAAAUCGAAUAUAAUCAUUUUUCAAUACUUAGGAUAACAGAUUCAGGCAAAGAUAAAACAUUAAAGGAAAAGUUAGUGAAAACUAUUAAUAUAUAGUGGAGGCAUCACGUUGUUAUGAACUUCAUUGAUCAAUACUGAUACCACUAAAAAUGGAACAACAUGUAAUUAUGUGCUCAAUGUGAUGAAUAUGAAGUAGACUGCACCACUCUGCAGUACAGUCAGGAAAUAAGAAACCAAGUCCAAUCAAAAUAGCCCUAAAGCUACCUUCCAGUUUAUAAAAAGUAUGAAGAAUAGAGGGGCAAUUAAAUGAUACCAUAAAGAGUCAAAUACAGGGCAUGCAACAUAGCUGCUGAUUGGAUUUAUUCAACAUGUCAGUGGCAUGAAUACAAUAGGAGGCAGGUAGGGAGAAGGCACUACCCUGAAUUAUGAGACUGAAGAGAUAUAAUAAACAAAUGCAAUGUGUGGACUUGGUUGGGAUCUUCAUUCAAAGACCAACUAUAAAAAGACAUUGUUGUGAGAAUUGAGGAAAUUUGAAUGAGAAAUGUAUUUUUAUCUAAUUUGUUAGCUGUGAUAAUAGUAUUGUGGGAGUAAGAAGCUAUUCAUAUUUCUAUAUAUAUAUACCAAGUACAUAGGAGUGAAAUAAUACAAAAUCUGGAAUUUGCCUUAAAAUUCCUCUGCAAAAUUAUAAAAAAGAACGAUGACAAACUAAAAAGGUGUAGUAUUCUUCUAUGGCUGCUAUAACAAAUGACCAAAAAACAUAGUGACUGAAAAUAACCCACAUUUAUUAUCUUACAGUUCCAUAGGUUAGAAGUUCAACAUGGGUCUCAUGAGAUCAAAAGCAAGGCCUUGGCAGGGUGACGUUUCUUUCUGGAGGUUCCAGGGGGAACUCUGUUUUCUUACUUUUUUUAGAUUCUAGAGGCUUCCCACAAUCCUUGGCUUAAGGUCCAUCUUUAAAGACAGCAACGUUUCAUCUCUCUACCUAUUCUUUCAUCCUUACAUCUUUCUCUAACUAUUCCUUUUCUUCUGUCUUCCACUUUUAAGAGCCUUUUUGAGUCUAUUGAGGCCAACUGGACAAUCAAGGAUUAUCUCCCUAUGUUAAGGUCAAUUGAUUAGUGACCUAAUUCCAUCUACAAUCACAAUUCCUCUUUGCCAUAUAAUGUAAAAUAUUCAUACCUCUAAGGAUUAGGACAUGGACAUCUUUGAGGGUCAUUAGUCAUCUUACCACAGGAAGGAAGGAAGGAAGGAAGGAAGGAAGGAAGGAAGGAAGGAAGGAAGGAAAGGGAGGAGAGGAGAGGAGAGGUAGGAGGGAAGAAGAAAAAAAUAGUAUGAAAAAAUCUUGAUAAAUUUGAAAACUGGGUGAAUAAUAUGUGGAAUUCUCUCUAUUUUUGUUAAUGUUGGAAAAUUUAAUAAAAACAAUGAACAGUGA